GGCUCGGCUCGGCUGCGCGGCCGCUGACGGGCGUGCGCUGGGGGCGCGGGGCGCGGGGCGCGGGCCUCGGCGGCGGCGGCGGCGGCGGCGGCGGAAGCCAGGUGCCCCCGCCCGCCCUGUCCUCUCGACGAGGCGGAGGCGUCGCCGCGGGCCAGGCCUCGGACUGCCGCGUCGGAGUGGACGCGGGGGGCGGCGGCGCGGGCGGACGCGGGCGGCGCGAAGCAGCGGGGCCCGCGGGGGCGCCCCGGCCGGGUCGGCGCGGACGGCACUCGGCGGACGCGGGCGGACGCUGGGCGGCCCCUCCCUGCCCGCGCGCCCGGGCGCCCCUGGCCGGCGCCGGGCCCCAGAGCGAUGACAUCGACGGGGAAGGACGGCGGCGCGCAGCACGCGCAGUAUGUUGGGCCCUACCGGCUGGAGAAGACGCUGGGCAAGGGGCAGACAGGUCUGGUGAAGCUGGGGGUUCACUGCGUCACCUGCCAGAAGGUGGCCAUCAAGAUCGUCAACCGUGAGAAGCUCAGCGAGUCGGUGCUGAUGAAGGUGGAGCGGGAGAUCGCGAUCCUGAAGCUCAUUGAGCACCCCCACGUCCUAAAGCUGCACGACGUUUAUGAAAACAAAAAAUAUUUGUACCUGGUGCUAGAACACGUGUCAGGUGGUGAGCUCUUCGACUACCUGGUGAAGAAGGGGAGGCUGACGCCUAAGGAGGCUCGGAAGUUCUUCCGGCAGAUCAUCUCUGCGCUGGACUUCUGCCACAGCCACUCCAUAUGCCACAGGGAUCUGAAACCUGAAAACCUCCUGCUGGACGAGAAGAACAACAUCCGCAUCGCAGACUUUGGCAUGGCGUCCCUGCAGGUUGGCGACAGCCUGUUGGAGACCAGCUGUGGGUCCCCCCACUACGCCUGCCCCGAGGUGAUCCGGGGGGAGAAGUAUGACGGCCGGAAGGCGGACGUGUGGAGCUGCGGCGUCAUCCUGUUCGCCUUGCUGGUGGGGGCUCUGCCCUUCGACGAUGACAACUUGCGACAGCUGCUGGAGAAGGUGAAGCGGGGCGUGUUCCACAUGCCGCACUUUAUCCCGCCCGACUGCCAGAGUCUGCUACGGGGCAUGAUCGAGGUGGACGCCGCACGCCGCCUCACGCUAGAGCACAUUCAGAAACACAUAUGGUAUAUAGGGGGCAAGAAUGAGCCCGAACCAGAGCAGCCCAUUCCUCGCAAGGUGCAGAUCCGCUCGCUGCCCAGCCUGGAGGACAUCGACCCCGACGUGCUGGACAGCAUGCACUCACUGGGCUGCUUCCGAGACCGCAACAAGCUGCUGCAGGACCUGCUGUCCGAGGAGGAGAACCAGGAGAAGAUGAUUUACUUCCUCCUCCUGGACCGGAAAGAAAGGUACCCGAGCCAGGAGGAUGAGGACCUGCCCCCCCGGAACGAGAUAGACCCUCCCCGGAAGCGUGUGGACUCCCCGAUGCUGAACCGGCACGGCAAGCGGCGGCCAGAACGCAAAUCCAUGGAGGUGCUCAGCGUGACGGACGGCGGCUCCCCGGUGCCUGCGCGGCGGGCCAUUGAGAUGGCCCAGCACGGCCAGAGUAAAGCAAUGUUCAGUAAAAGCCUGGAUAUCGCUGAGGCCCAUCCCCAAUUCAGCAAAGAAGACAGGUCUCGGUCCAUCAGCGGUGCCUCCUCAGGCCUUUCCACCAGCCCACUCAGCAGCCCCCGGCCUAUUAGGAAGCUUGUCCUGCCCCCACCGCCCCCCGAGCCGCCCUUCGUGGCCCGCCCCCUGGCCACCUCCACGGAGCCCGAAGCUUGUGGGAGCGCCUCGAGGCCUGGACACGUCCUCCCUCUGCAGGCCGCCCUGCGGCCCGACCCCAAGACCCAGACCUUGCCGUGCAAGGCCAAGCUGACCGACAAGCCUCUGCAGGGCACCAAGUCCAACCCCUUCCCGGCCAGCACCCCAGCCCGGCCUCCCGCCACUGGCCUUUGUCCCCAGCUGGCACCACCCCUGGGCCCGCCUGCCCUGCGGGUGCCCCCCCGGCCCCCACCCGCCGGGAUUGAACCAAACACCAAAUCUGUCCCCACCAUACAGGUGACCCCUCACCCCUCACCAAGGGGCAGUCCCCUCCCCACCCCCAAGGGGACACCUGUCCACACGCCAAAGGAGAGCCCGGCUGGCACGCCCAACCCCACGCCCCCGUCCAGCCCCAGCGUCGGAGGGGUGCCCUGGAGGGCGCGGCUCAACUCCAUCAAGAACAGCUUUCUGGGCUCACCCCGCUUCCACCGCCGGAAACUGCAAGUUCCGACGCCGGAGGAGAUGUCCAACCUGACACCAGAGUCGUCCCCAGAGCUGGCGAAGAAGUCCUGGUUUGGGAACUUCAUCAGCCUGGAGAAGGAGGAGCAGAUCUUCGUGGUCAUCAAAGACAAACCUCUGAGCUCCAUCAAGGCUGACAUCGUGCACGCCUUCCUGUCGAUUCCCAGUCUCAGCCACAGCGUCAUCUCCCAAACGAGCUUCCGGGCCGAGUACAAGGCCACGGGGGGGCCAGCCGUGUUCCAGAAGCCGGUCAAGUUCCAGGUUGAUAUCACCUACACGGAGGGUGGGGAGGCGCAGAAGGAGAACGGCAUCUACUCCGUCACCUUCACCCUGCUCUCAGGCCCCAGCCGUCGCUUCAAGAGGGUGGUGGAGACCAUCCAGGCCCAGCUGCUGAGCACACACGACCCGCCUGCGGCCCAGCACUUGUCAGACACCACUAACUGUAUGGAAAUGAUGACGGGGCGGCUUUCCAAAUGUGGCAGCCCAUUGAGUAACUUCUUUGACGUAAUUAAACAACUUUUUUCAGACGAGAAGAACGGGCAGGCGGCCCAGGCCCCCAGCACGCCCGCCAAGCGGAGUGCCCACGGCCCACUCGGUGACUCCGCGGCCGCUGGCCCUGGCCCCGGAGGGGACGCCGAGUACCCAACGGGCAAGGACACGGCCAAGAUGGGCCCGCCCACCGCCCGCCGCGAGCAGCCUUAGACACACUAGCCCCCCCCCCCAGCACAGCACUGACAGCGGCUGCCUCGCCGCCCGCCGCCCGCCCUGCCCCGAGUGGACCCGCGGCCGCGCCGCCCGUCCGUCCAGACUGUUCUCAGAGCCUGGGAGGAAAGGAAAGGGGCGUUGGGGCCGGCCUGUGGGCUGCGCCACCCGCGCCCGCUCUCUUUUCUCUCUGUCUCUGCCUCUGCCUGUCUCUGACAGCAUCGCUUGUUUCCACUCUGAUACCAGGAAUUAUCCCGAAAAGUUAACAUGUCACCUCCACGAGGCCAUCCUCUGUGACCGAAGGCAGCUGCUGCGGACCCGCCCUCCCUCCGCUCCUGCUGUUGCUGCCGGGCAGUGAGGCCCAGCCCAGCGCCCCGUCCACCCCGCGGCAGCUCCUCGCCUCAGCUCCGCACGGCCCGUGGGAGGAAGGCCAGGCUCGGGGGAGCCUCCUCCAGCCCGGCCGACCCGGACUCCCGGUCACCUGACCCCUCAGCAAGAACAGCCUGCCUGGUGGCCUUCUGGGGCCAGGACCCCUGGUGGGCAACGUAGCCACAGGAACAGGCCCCGUCCACCGCCUCCACGCCGCACCUGGAGGCCUCCUCGCAGGCCCGUGCCCCGCCUCCCUGGCUGCGCCGCCUCCGUGUAGUCUUGGCCUCCUCAGGCUGCCUCCCGUCCUCUCGUCUCACCCGCGCCUCCCUUGCCUCAUCUGGGGCGGCUGUGGGCUCUGGCGCUCCUCUCUGGCUGAGGUGGAAACAGAGACACCCUGCGGCACCAGAGCCUUCCCAGCAGGCCAGGCCGCUGGGCUGGGAUCAGUGUUAUUUAUUUGCCGUUUUAAUUUAUGGAUUCUCCGCACCUCUGUUCAGGGAAGGGCGGCGGCCACAUCCCCUGCCGUCUGCGUGUCUCAGGCAGUGGGGGGGCUGGGGCCAGGGCGCCCUCUGAGGACAGAGCUGGUGGGGCGCGGGGGGGCUGGCGAGCUACUGUAAACUUUAAAGAAUUCCUGCAAGAUAUUUUUAUAAACUUUUUUUUCUUGGUGGUUUUUGGAAAAGGGUGUGGGGGUGGGGGCGCCGCUGGGGCAGGGCCAGGUUUUGUGUUUUAGUCCCUUGCUCCUGCUUCUUUCUACACACACAUCUAAAGACGGUGCGGCUCGCUCUGUCAUGGGUUCCGUCUCUCUGUGGAGAAGCAGCUCCACCUCUGGGGGGGCUCGGGGCAGAGGGGCGGUGUCUUGUAGCGGGCGGCAGCGCCAGCGCCCCUCUGUCAGGCUGGGGCAAUCUUGGUUUUGUGUCCAAAGGUGAAGGGGUAGGAGGAGGGCCCUCAGCUGGCCCUCCCCACACACAGGACGGCAGGGGCACUGUGAGGCUUUUCUUAUUAAAAUGAAAAAAUUGAAAAAAAAGGACAAAGAGUCGGUGGCGCUCCUCUGCAGGGCGUUCUGUGCAGAGCGAGGCCCAGGGCGCAGCCCUCAGAGGGCUGCAGGCCCACCCUGCCCAGUGCCCGCCGCCGUGCUUCACCCCAGCUCCAGCUUCUGUGUUCCCUUCCGCCCAUGUGCCCAGCCCUCCCAGGCGGGCACAGCCCGGGUGCGGCGGCCGUGGGGGACGGCGGGUCUGAUGCAUGCCUCUGCCAUGGAGUCGUCUGUCUGCUUCGGUGCCUGCCCCUGCCUCCCACCCACCUCGUGUAUAGAUUUUAACGCUUCUGUUAACAUUAGACCUCUGCCACAGGCUGGGAUUUCUAUACAUAAGAACAAAAGCAAACACCUAGGACAGCAAACGCCAGGCGGUACAGGCGGGAAGGGGCUCUCCACGGAGAUCGAGGACACGAAGCAAACUGCCUCUUGCUUGCCUUCCCCUUUUGUGCUUCGGACACACGCGGACUCCAGCAGGCGCCACGGAAAUGGGCAAGCCCCUGCAGUGUACCCCUGUCAUAACUGUGAGCAGCUGCAGCUCCGGAACAAUAAAUCCCUUCCGCAAAGACA